GUGCUGUUGUAAUUAGCUUAAUUAAUCAAAUGUAUCUUUGAUGAUCCAUUUAUUAAUUCAUUUUUUUUUCUUCUAGACAGCAAAGGACUGAAUUUUGUUAAAACCCACCCUUGCUCAGAGGGCAUUUAUAAAGAAAACAACCUCCACAAUGAAACAAAAAUUCAGGGGAGAUGCGGUGUGAGGUCUGCUCCAGGCCGUGGGACGCUUCGGCCGAGGAUACCGCAAUGGAUCAGGAAGAGGGGCUGAAGGCCUUGGACAAUAUUGUCACUCAAUUCAACGCCUAUGAAGAUUUCCUGGACUCGCAGAUCACUACUGUGGACUUGUACUACCUGGAGGAUGAAACCCUGGCCCGCCAGUUGGUGGAGCUAGGCUACCGAGGGACUGGAGAGAGAGUGAAAAGGGAAGAUUUUGAAGCAAGGAAAGCGGCUAUAGAGAUUGCAAGACUGGCUGAAAGAGCUCAGCAAAAGACGCUAACAAGUGCUGGUAAAGACCUACAAGAUAAUUUUCUGACGGCCCUGGCAAUGAGAGAAGAAGACAAUCGCAGUGGAAAACUGAGUCUAAAUCAACAGGAGACUGAUGCUGCUCAUAUCUUGAAGAAGCAACUGGCAGUCAUAUGGAAACCACAAAGCAAAACCUAUCAUAGGUAUGUGAAAAUAAAAAGCAAGCAAUCAAAACAACACUGAAGAAAAUCACUUAGCUAUAAAAGAAGACAGAAAAAGAGAAAGAGACAGAAGAUCUAUGAAAAAACUAGAAAACAGUUAACAAGAUGGCAGUAGUAAAUCCUUACCUGUCAAUAAUUACUUUGAAUGUAAAUGGAUUAUGUUCUCCCAUCAAAAGGUGUAAGAUAGCUGAAUGAAUUUAAAAAACAAAAAAACAAGAUCCAAAUAUAUGCCACCUACAAGAGACUGACUUCACUUGUAAGGACACACAUAGACUUAAAGUGAAGGGCUGGAGAAAAAUACUGCAUGUAAAUGGUAGCCAAACACAAACUGGAGUGGCCAUUCUUAUAUCAGAUUAUAUAGACUUUAAGUAAAACUGUAAAAAGAAAAAGUAACAUAAUUGUAUCAUUAUAAAUGGGUCAAUUCAGCAAGAGGAUAUAACAAUUACAAAUAUAUACGUACCCAAUAUCCAAGCUGAUGAAGAUAUAAAGUAAAUAUAAAUAAAUUUGAAGGGAGCAAUAGAUUGCCAUAUAAUAAAUUUAGGGGAGUUAAACACCCCACUUCUGGAAAUGGGCAGAUCAUUCACACAGAAAAUCAAUAAGGAAACAGUAAACUAAAAGCAUAAUCUAGAUCAAGUGGACAUAACAAAUAUAUGCCCAACAUUUCACCCCAAAGCUGCAGAAUAUAUAUUAUUUUAUUUGCAACUCCACAUGGAACAUUCUCUAGGAUAGAUUAUAUGUUAGGCCACAAAGCAAGUCUUAACAAAUUUAUGAAGGUUGAAAUCAUAUCAAGUAGCUAUUCUGACCUCAAUUAAUUAGAAUUAACAUAAAUUAAUUAGAGGAGACACUUUGGAAAAUUUGGCAAAUGGAAAUGCUCUUGAACAACUAAUAGGUCAAUGAAGAAAUUGGAAAGAAAAUUUAAAAAUUUCUUAAGACAAAUGAAAAUUGAAUCACAACAUACCCAAACUUACCAGAUACAGCAAAAGCAGUUCUAAGAAGGAAGCAUGUAGCUGUAAACAGUGACAUUACAAAAGGUAAAAGAUCUCAAAUAAACAACCUAACAUUGUACUUCAAGGAACUGCAAAAAACAGGAAUAAACUAAGCCCAAAGUUAGUAAAAGGAAGGAAAUAAUAAAAAUCAGGACAGAAAUAAAAUAAUAGAGCCUGGAAAAAUAAUAGAAAAAUAUAUAUUUUUGAAAAGAUAAACAAAAUAAAACUUUAGCUUCACUAACUGAGAAUGAAAUAGGAGUCAAAUAAGUAAAAUGAAGAACAGGAAAAGGAGAUAUUACAAUUGACACAACAGAAAUUCAAAGGGCCAUAAGAGAUUAUUAUGAACAUUUAUAUACCAACCAUUUCAGUAACCUAGAGAAACAGAUAAAUUAUUUGAUGCUUUUAUUAUGAAGACAUAAAAAAUCUUUACAGACCAAUAACCAGUAAAAAGAUUGAAUCAGCAAUAAAGUCUCCUAUCAAAGAAGAGUCUGGGACAUGGUGACAUCACUGCUGAAUUCUAUCAAAUAUUUAAAGAAGAACUAAUAAAAAUUUUGCUUAACUCUUCCAAAAAAUUGAGGAGAUGAAACUUUCAAACUUAUUUUAUCAGGCCAGCAUUACCUUGAUACCAACAAACAAACAAACAAACAAACAAAAAACUACAAAAAACCCUACAGACCAAUAUCUCUGAUUAAUAUAAAUGCAAAAAUCCUCAACAAAAUAUUAGCACACUGAAUUCAAUGGUACAUUGAAAAUAUUAUUCAUCAUGAUCAAGUGGUAUUCAUUCCAGUGAUGCAAGGAUGGUCCUAUAUAUGCAAAUCGGUAAAUGUAAUACAUUACAUGAACAGAAUGAAGGACAAUAAGCAUAUAAUCAUUUCCGUAGGUGCAAAAAAAUUUGGAAAAAUUUGGCAUCCUUUCAUGAUUAAAAAACUCUAAAUAAAUUAGGUAUAGAAGGAAUGUACUUCAACACAAUUGAAGCUAUAUAUGAUAAACCCCAUAGCUAACUCAAUGGGGAGAAGUUGACAGCUUUUCCUCUAAGACACAGAGUAAGAUAAGGAUGUCCAUGUUAACCACUUCCAUUCAAUAUAGUAUUGGAUGUGCUAGCCAGAGCAAUUAGGCAAAAGAAAGAAAUAGAAGACAUACAAAUUGGAAAGGAAGAAAUUAAAUUGUCCCUGAUUGCAGAAGGCAUGACCCUAUAUACAGAAAAUUCUAAAGACUUUACAAAAAGAAACCUGUGAGAAUUAUCUAGUAAAUUGAGUAAAGUUGCAGGAUACAAAAUCAACAUACAACACUCGGUAGUGUUUCUAUUCACUAAUAGCAAGCUAUCUGAAAAAGAACAAGAGAACCAUACCAUUUACAAUACUUACAAGAAAUAUUUAGGAAUAAAUUUAACCAAGGAGGUGAAUGAUCUCUACCCUAAAAGCCAUAAAACAAUGAUGAAAGAAAUUAAAGAAGACACACAUAAAUGGAAAUAUAUUCUUUGUUCAUAGAUUGGAAGAUUUAAUAUUGUUAACAUGUCCAUACUACCCAAAGCAAGCUACAGAUUCAACAGAAUUCCUAUCAAAAUACCAAUAACAUUUUUCACAGAAAUAGAAAAAACAAUUCUAAAAUUCAUAUGGAAUAACAAAAAAUUCCUGAAAAGCCAAAGCAUUUUGAACAAGAAGAAGAAAGCUAAAGACAUUACACUACCUGACUUCAAAAUAUGUUACAAAGCUAUAGUGACCAAAACAGCAUGGUACUGGCAUAAAAAUAGACACACAGAGCAAUUAAACAAUAGAGAGCACAGAAAUAAAUCCAUGCAUUUACAGCUGGCUGAUUUUUGACAGCGGUGUCAAGAGCACACAAUAGGAAAAGGACAGCCCUUUCAAUAAAUGCUUUUGGGAAAACAGGAUAUUCACAGGCAGAAAAAUAAAAUUAGAAUCUUAUCUCACACCAUAUAUAAAAAUCAACUUAAAAUGGAUUAAAGACUUACAUGUAAGACCCAAAACUAUGAAACUACUAGAAUAAAACUUAGGAGAAAAACUAUGACAUUUAUCUGGGCAAUGACUUUUUUGGAAAUGACCCCAAAGCACAGGCAACAAAAGCAAAAAUUGACAAAUAAGAUUGCAUCAAACUCAAAAGCUUCUGUGCAGCAAAGAAAACAACCAACAGAGCAAAGAGACAACGUGCAGAAUGGAAGAAAAUGUUUGCAAACUGUAUAUCUGUUAUGGGGUUAAUUUCCAAAAUACGUAAGAAAUUCAAACAAUUCAAUAGCAAGAAGGCAAACUAUUCAAUAAAAUUAGGAGCCAUGAAACUGAACAGACAUUUCUUAAGGCAUACAAAUGGUUAAAAAGUAUGUGAAACAAAAGCUCAAUAUUACUAAUCAGGGAAACAUAAAUUAAAAACACAAUGAGAUAUUACCUUAGAGCAGCUAGAAUGCGUAUCUUCAAGAUAAAAGAUAAGUGUUGGCAAAAUGUGCGGCAAAGGGAACCCUUGCACGCUGUUGGUGAGAAUGUAAAUUGAUGCAGCCAUUAUGGAAAACAGUAUGGAUGUUCCUCAAAAAAUUAAAAAUAAAACUGCCAUAUAAUCCAGCAAUCCCACUACUGAAUAUGUAUCUAAAGAAAUGAAAUCAGUAUGUUGAAAAGAUUCCUUUACUUUUGUGUUUAUUGCAGAAUUAUUCACAAAAGCCAAGAUAUGGAAUCAACCUAAGUUUCCAUUACUGAAUGAGUGGAUUAAAAAAUGUGGACACAAUGGAAUACUAUUAAGCCAUAAAAAAGAAGGAAAUCCUGUCAUUUGCAACAACAUGUAUUAACCUGGAGGACAUUAUGUUGAGUGAAAUAGGCGGGGCACAGAAAGACAAAUACCACCUGAUCUUGCUCAUAUGUGGCAUCUUAAAAAGUUAAACUCACAGAAGUAGAAAGUAGAAUAGUGUUACCAGGGGCUGGGGUAUUUGAGAGUCAGGGGGGAGAGAUGUUGGUCAAAGAAUAUAAAAUUUCAGUUAGAUAAGAGAAAUAAGUUCAAGAGCUCUAUUGUACAACUUGGUGACUGUAGUUUAUAAUAUAUUGUAUUCUUGAGAAAUGCUGAGAGAGUAGAUGUUAACUGUUCUCACUACAAAAAUCAAAAAUGAUAGCUAUAUGAGGGAAUACAUAUGCUAGUCAGUCUGUCUGUAUAUAUAUUUCAAAUACUGUUCUCUACACAAUAAUAUAUGCACUUUUAUCUGUCAAUUUAUAAAAAAUUGGCCAAGUGCAGUGGCUCACACCUGUAACCCCAACACUUUGGGAGGCCGAGAUGGGCGGAUCACUUGAGGUCAGGAGUUCAAGACCAGCUUGGCGAACAUAGUGAAACCUGGUGUCUACUAAAAAUACAAAAAUUAGCCAGGUAUGAUGGUGUGCACCUGUAGUCCCAGCUACUUGGAAGGCUGAGGCAGGAGAAUCGCUGGAGCCAGGGAGACAGGGGUUGCAGUGAGUCAUGAUUAUGCCAUUGUGCUUUAGCCUGGAGACUCUGUAUCUGGAAAAAAAAAAAAACAAAAAAAACAAAAAAAACCCAGAAAAAUUUAUUUAAAAAUUGUAGAGAAUAGAACCAACUGAAACUUUUCUGAAUACAGCUAUUUUCAUUGAAAUUUUUAAAAUGUUUAGGUGGAAUAAAUUCUAGAAUGAAAAUAGUUUAAGAGAAAAUUCGUGAACUGAUCAUAGGACUGAGAAUUUUACCCAGAAUGCAGCAAAGAAAGGCAAAGAGAUAGGAAUUUUGGAGAAAAAAAGAAUCCUCCACGGGAUAAUGAGAUUGAAAGGCUCCAACAUACUUUGAACUGACCUUCCAGAAGAGAAUGGAAGUAAUGAUACAAAAGCAGUAUUUUUGUGUAUACGUUUUUCUUUUCUUGUGGUAGGGAGUAGAAAAGCCGUACACAGUAAAUUAACAGUAAAGUAAAAUCAUUCAAAAGUGAACCUCAUCAUUCUAUAUCUGUGAAAGUUGCAUAUGAAUAUUCUGAUAACUUUUCUCUUAUCAGAAAAGUCUUACCUUUAAAGAUGUCUUAAAACGAAAAUUCACAUCAUGCUUUAAAUUUGUUCUCUACUAAACAAUUUGGUGAACAGCAUAUAUUUUAAAAGUUCUGGGUUAUUAGAGUGAUGACUACAUUAAUAAUAGUGUUUUUUUAAUAAAUUAUAAAAUGUUGAUUUUAUGAAACAUUAUGUUUUUAUAAUAUCGUAGAAAAUACUGUAGUGGCAACUAAUGCUAAUUUUCUGUGAAUAUGGGAAUCAUUUCAAGGAAAGACAAAGAUAUAAUGAAGUGUGCUGUAUAUAUGUUUAAUUAUGCAGUACAAGGGAUUAAAGUAUUUUAUUCAUGAAAUUAAUGAUCCACAUAUUAUCGAGUAAUAUAUUGACAAUAGAAGCAUAAUAUAAGUACUUAAAUGAAAUUAUUUCAUUAAUAGCAGAUUUUCCAUGAAACAAAUGCCAAGAAUAGACAGACUUGUAAAUUAUUUUUUUCUUACACAUACAUACUUAAGAGUUACGUUAACAUAUUACUUCAGGACAAGAUGUUUUAGAAAUUAAUUAGGAUUUAAAUGAAAAUAGACCCUCACCAAUUUCCACUAAUGACAGGAAGAUGCUAUUUAGACUGUUAAAAUAUUAAAAUUAGAAAGCAUAAAAGAGGUACAAUCAAUUGCAGGGCUAUGCAUAAAAUAUAGUUGUUUCCUUUAUUAGAGUAGUGUUGUUUAAAUUAAUUAUAAAAUAACAUUAUGUUCACAUCAAUUGGCCCAGCCUUUAGUAUAUUAAGCUGUCAUAGUCACUAGUUGAUUUUACAGUUAUUAUUUAUGAAAGUUGCCAUUAUUCAGUAUUUAUAAAAGUUGCCAAGGUGGUAAAUAAGUAACCUUUAUCAUUAUUUUAUAAUUUAUUUUUAUAAGAAACAUUUGUUGGUAUAGCAUUAUAUAAUUCAUGUCUUAUUAGUUUAUUUAAAUAUGUAUUUGGCUGAUAAAUUGUAUAAAUUGUAUGAGAGUCAGUGCAAAUACUUUGAACAGAUACCUACAUAAACAUCAAGUGCAAAUUAUAAAGUAAAGAGUAAGUCUAGAAAUUGGUAAAUAUUCAAACUAAAUAUUAAAAGAAAAAAUAUAUUUUGGGAUUCCUGGUUGUUUGCAUUUCUUCCUUUUUAAUAAUUUGGCAUUAAUCUAGCAUUUUUUCUUUAUGCUUCAUGAUAGAUUAUAAUUUUAACAGCUCCAAUAUUUAAGGCUGUAUCUUACAUUUUGAAAAAGAGAAGGUACUUCAUUUUGUCUCUUACAACAUUCAACUACUGUCAUAAAUCCAUUUGUAUAAACAUAUUACUUUCAAGUUAGUCAAUUUACUUCAUUUUUCUUUCAAAUACUUUUUCUUUUUAAUCUAUGUCAUCAUGUUUUGUGAUUGCUUUAGCCACGUGAACAAUAAUAAAAGAAUUUUGGAAAAUCUGA